AGGAACACUAUCACCGAUUCUGGGGAAAAAAAAGAAAAAGCCAAUAGCAUUAACAUAAUACUCUGCAACCUUAAAGGUUUGCAGUUGAUAAGGAAUAAUUUAAUGUGCCCUAUAAAACCCACAGUUUUGGAAUUGCUCCAGCUUUUUAUUUUUAGCUGUGGCUUUUAGUUAAUGAGAAGAGGUGAAAAGUAUAGUUUCUCCUGGUCUCUGCUUGAAAUCACAGAAACUUUCCGCGCUGUGAAAGUUCAGGGGAUUUUGGGAGACCAUCCUUAUGAAUUGGAUGGUGGUGUCUCCUCCUCUUUGUUCAGGCCUCUUUUUCUAGAGAAUAGCAAAGAAUGGUGAGUUGAUUACCUUCAGAUUUUAACCAAACUGUAAUUGCUCUGAUAUUGUCAAAUGCACCUAGGGACAGUGUUGCAGUAUUUUGAAACCUUACACAGGAAACAAAAUAGCAGCUUUGGAGGCAGGGAAGAAUGCAUUAGUUUCUGAGUCUAAGGAAGCCAGAAGGAAGCCCGCCCACCCACUCUCUAGCUUUCAUAUUCCCUCAGCCACCUCCCAGAUCUUCCAUUGCUGUGCUAUAAAUAGCCAGUGUUUAGGCAGGGCGUUGCUUUCUUCCCUUGCCUUUGAAGACUUUCUGCAGGCCCUGGAAUUGCCUUUGUUCCUCUGUCUGCCCACUUUGCCAGUGUGAAGCAGGUUUUCAUGGGAUUCUACUGGGGUAAACCAAAAGCAGCAGAAAAAGUGUGAAACGGCAACUCCAAACUAACAUGGCAGUCAGACUGUGUGAUGUGGCUUCUCUGCUUAGAAGUGGUUCGUGGGCAGCAGAGCCUUGGACCGGGCAGGUAAUUGCUGCCAUGGAAACACAACUGUCUAAUGGGCCAACUUGCAAUAACACAGCCAAUGGUCCAACCACCAUAAACAACAACUGUUCGUCACCAGUUGACUCUGGGAACACAGAAGACAGCAAGACCAACUUAAUAGUCAACUACCUUCCUCAGAACAUGACACAGGAGGAACUAAAGAGUCUCUUUGGGAGCAUUGGUGAAAUAGAGUCCUGUAAGCUUGUAAGAGACAAAAUAACAGGGCAGAGCUUGGGAUAUGGCUUUGUGAACUACAUUGACCCCAAGGAUGCAGAGAAAGCUAUCAACACCCUGAAUGGAUUGAGACUUCAAACCAAAACAAUAAAAGUUUCCUAUGCUCGCCCAAGUUCAGCUUCUAUCAGAGAUGCAAAUUUAUAUGUCAGCGGACUUCCAAAAACAAUGACCCAGAAGGAGUUGGAACAGCUUUUUUCACAAUAUGGACGCAUUAUUACUUCUCGUAUUCUUGUCGACCAGGUCACUGGCAUAUCAAGGGGUGUAGGGUUUAUUCGAUUUGACAAGCGAAUUGAGGCAGAAGAAGCUAUCAAAGGCCUAAAUGGCCAGAAACCUCCCGGUGCCACGGAGCCAAUCACUGUAAAGUUUGCUAAUAACCCAAGCCAAAAAACCAAUCAGGCCAUCCUUUCCCAGCUGUACCAGUCUCCAAACAGAAGGUAUCCAGGACCGCUAGCUCAGCAGGCACAGCGUUUUAGGUUGGACAAUCUGCUCAAUAUGGCUUAUGGAGUAAAGAGCAGGUUUUCUCCAAUGACCAUUGACGGAAUGACCAGUUUGGCUGGAAUUAAUAUCCCUGGGCACCCUGGAACAGGGUGGUGUAUAUUUGUGUACAACCUGGCUCCUGACGCAGAUGAGAGUAUCCUGUGGCAAAUGUUUGGGCCUUUUGGAGCUGUCACCAAUGUGAAGGUCAUCCGUGACUUUAACACCAAUAAAUGCAAAGGUUUUGGAUUUGUGACUAUGACAAACUAUGAUGAGGCUGCCAUGGCGAUAGCUAGCCUCAAUGGAUACCGUCUGGGAGACAGAGUACUGCAGGUCUCCUUUAAGACAAACAAAACGCACAAAGCCUAAUGAGCUCUUGUCCUCAGUCCAUUUAUAUAUGAAAACUAUACAACAAAGGCAAGUUAAGAGAAACUUUAUACAUUAGUAAAUGUCUUUGUAAGUCAGUGUUGAGAUGGGGAUAAAAUGACUACUUAGCAUCCUAAGAAAUAUGUGAGAUUUUUUAUUGCUAGUAUUUGAAUUAAAACUUCUUAAAUAUCUUUUAUGUUUGAAUAUGGACAAGAGGUACAGGGUUUUUACCUGUCACAUUGCAUUCUAUUGCCUUCUUUGAAGAAGGUGGACCUUUUAAAGUGUUUCAGCUAAGGGAAGACAUUUCUUUUCUUUUUACAUAACUGCCUUGAACCUGUGAGUAAAUAUUGAGGCUUUGUGUUGUAAUUCUUCAGUUGGUUGUGUCUUUUUUUUCCCCCCUUUUUUUCCUUUUUCUGAUUAGCUUUGUGUUUGGUUUACAUUUAAAGCAUUGCUGUUAUGUCUGUUUAAGAAAAGUAUUUUGAAGUUUACAUUUUUAUUUAUGAAGUUUAAAACAGUAUUUAUUUUGUAAUUAUGAUUUGGGUUGGGGAAGGGGGGGCUACAUUAUAAACGCUUAUUGUAAGAAUACUGGAGAACUUUUCGUAAAGCAGUACCUUGCCAAAGAGAUAAGAGCCUCUUUGAUGUGGGUUUAAAAAAAGCAUCUAUUUUUAUAAAAAAGAAAAUUUGGAGAAACUUUUUACUGGUCCUGGAACAAAUAUUUUGACUUGAAUACUUUGAGAAAUCUCUUCAUAUGACACCUAGUGAGCUUUUAAAAUUUACCAGGAAAUUUGCAGCGGUUGGAAAAUUUAGAAAGAUUUAUGGUGUAGAAAAUACUUUUGAGAUCUUUGUAUGAAAGGAGUAGAAUCAAUGGGGGGAAACACUGCUGGUUUCAUUUUUGUAAUCACCAGUGGAGCGUCUGAUCAUCCUGGUUAUUAUGUGAUAGGUGGCUCACAUUGAUUUGUGAUUUUGAAACAAAUAAAAAAAAUUUACAAAAGAAUAUAUAAGAGCAGGCAAGAAAUUUAAAUUACCGAGAGAUGGGGGAAAAAAUCUGUUCUUCCUAAAGAAAUCCCUUCAGAUAGAGCUCAUGGUGUUUAGUGAUGUACUUGCAGUAUUGUUUGAAGAAUUGUUUUGUCUUAAGGAAAAAAGACGUUGCACAUGAUUUGUACUGCAGCAAAUCAGCAAAAGUGAUCUGAGUUGGAUAUAUUUGAAGGUAUUUUGAAAGUUACGUUCAAGGCUAACACCUGAGCUUUGUGUAAUGUAAAUAAGACCUUGUGUUUAUGAACCUUUCAGCUAAUUUAAUUUUUUUUCCCUUACAUGCCAAGUGAUGUUCAGGUUUUGAAUGUUUUUGUAUCAGUUUUUUCCUUUGUAAAUGGCAUUAACAUUGUUACUUGAGGUCUUGCUUAAUCACUUUUGUUGUCCUGAGGACUUGAAUUUACAGUGCAUCAGAUUUGUUGCAAAUUUUGUCUGUAGAUAGUCUAGCUUCAGCUGUUUAUGGUGAUGCUACAUUUUGGUUUAUAAAUAUGUUUGUGGUAUAAAAAAAUGAGUAUAACCAUAGGUUUUGAACAAAUUUCCUUACAUUUUUCAUACAAAAAUCAUAAAUAUCUGUAUGCUAUUGAAAUUUAACUUUGUAUGAUGCUUAAAAACCACUAUUUGGGGAAAUAAUAAAAUAAGUCUUUACCAUGUAUGAAAGAAAUUUUAAAAAAUACAAAAUAUUUUCUGAUUAGCAUCUAGCUUAUAAUAAAUUUUCAAAAAAGCUGAAGGCAAAAAUGCCUUCAUCAGGAUGCACUGAGAACUAUAUAGUUACGUCCUGCUUUUUGUAUAAACUGAGAUGCUCACAUGCUUCCCCUUAGAACAGGCAAUGUGCUAUGCAUAACAUAGUUGUACAUUAUCUUUGCGGUUGCUUUGAGUUUUAUUUUUUAUUAUUUAAAAUUGUAGUUAUAAAAUUUUUCAGUAUAGUACAGUACAUAUACUGUGAGGCGCGUGCUAAAGUGAAUAAGCGAGUUUUCAUGCUGACCCACUCAAUGCUAUUCAGAAAUCAAUUGGCUUAGCACUUUCUCAUAUCCUUAGGUGCAUUUAGAUUGCCAGAGUUAACCUUCUGCGUUUAAAAAAAGAAAAACACUAAAAAAUAAAAUACAUGUAUAUACUUAAAAAAAAAUAAUAAGGUUUCCCUCAAGGGAAAACAGCAGCUACAUGCUUCUUUCCUAUACUACUGUAGCAAACCAAGGCAUUGAUGAGAGGGCAUGCAAAUUGUGCUUCACUUUACAGUGUUUUAUCAGAGCACUUAAUAAAAUGUAAGGCUGGUAUUUAUUUGAAGUUGUACAGUAUGACUUAAUUCACAUCUGUUGGAAUAGAAAAUAUAUUCUGUUGAGUAUUUAAGAGGCUGUACAUGUUUUCUUUUGUGUUUGGAUUCUUUGUACUUUUUCAUGUUCAGUACAUCAAUAAACAAAGUUGAAGGGAAA